AGUCAGCUUUCUGCCGGGCUCCGAACUAGGACUGCUGGGUGCUCCCUCCUACCUGCCUGGUAGGGGGCGCAUUUGAGGGCGACGUCGGAGCCAUAGCCGUGAUCCCGUGGACACCUCCAGCUCCUCAGGCCUCUCCCCAUAGAAGAGAGCCAGCUGCAGGGAGAUCAGAUUCCUCAUGGAGGAACCAAGGCACUCGAAACGACCUCGCUUCCUGGCCCCAAAUCAAGCUUCAGGUGGGCCUCCUACAGAGCCAGGCUGCUCUGGUGUGGACCGUGAAGACCCUGUAGACCCAGUCCAACCGGCAAAACCCACUGCUUAUGUGAAACCCAUGAGACGGGAGCCCCCAGCUCGCGCACAGCCAGCUCCUCCUGCAGGAAGAGGCCAGCGUGGGGGAGGAAGCUGGCGGGCAGGUCGAGGCCGCGGCAGUGGGGCUGGGCUUCUCAGGGCCCUGGGCGAGAGAGUGGGGCCAGGCAUGUACCUAGUCCAUCUGAAUGACCAUGGAGAGCUAGGCUACCAGGGGCAACUGGAAGCCAGGCAGACCCCAGCCUUCUCUUUUACUGAAGCAGCUCUUAUGCCUGGAAUUGUGCAGGAAGGCCCCGGCCCCCAUGCAGCCCAGCCUGAGGUGGGGCUUCAGGAGCCACCUCCUGCUCCUGGGCCUGUGGCUGUGGCCAGGCAGACCAUGUUGGCCCCCUCUCCCUCCCUCAGUUUCAGGCCUCCGGGUGGCUCAUCUACUUUGUGCAUCGUGCAGACCUCUAAUAGCACCAUCGUGCAGAGUGUCCCAGUGUUCCCUGCCCACUCUGCACACUAACCUCUGUCAUCCGUAUUGCUGCCAGCCUUCUUUUCUUCCACCUGGUCUUUCCCCCUAUCCCCAAACUCUAGCCCCAUUUCUGCUCCACUCCUCCCUGCCCAUCCCAGUCAGAGCCCUUACUUUGUGUUGUCAUGAGCCUCCAAGUCCUCCUCCCAGGAUCCUGACAGUAGUCCAUCUGCUUCCAAUUCCCCUCUUGCCUCCGCUUUGUAUGUUCUGUCAAAAAUACACAUGCAUGGAGUUCCUCAAUGCUUAUUCAAAUAAACCAGCAGCUCUCUGA